GUGGCUUCAGGAAGAGGAGGGCAAGGUGUCUGGCUGCGCGUUUGGCUGCAAUGAGCUCGGCCUCGGGGCUCCGCAGGGGGCACCCGGCAGGUGGGGAAGAAAACAUGACAGAAACAGAUGCCUUCUAUAAAAGAGAAAUGUUUGAUCCGGCAGAAAAGUACAAAAUGGACCACAGGAGGAGAGGAAUUGCUUUAAUCUUCAAUCAUGAGAGGUUCUUUUGGCACUUAACACUGCCAGAAAGGCGGGGCACCUGCGCAGAUAGAGACAAUCUUACCCGCAGGUUUUCAGAUCUAGGAUUUGAAGUGAAAUGCUUUAAUGAUCUUAAAGCAGAAGAACUACUGCUCAAAAUUCAUGAGGUGUCAACUGUUAGCCACGCAGAUGCCGAUUGCUUUGUGUGUGUCUUCCUGAGCCAUGGCGAAGGCAAUCACAUUUAUGCAUAUGAUGCUAAAAUCGAAAUUCAGACAUUAACUGGCUUGUUCAAAGGAGACAAGUGUCACAGCCUGGUUGGAAAACCCAAGAUAUUUAUCAUUCAGAAUUUGGCUGCAAAGUGAUGAUUUUCCACCUCCAGAAACUCUCCCACAUUUACCAGUAGAUGCUCAGCACCUCACUGUAAGUAAGAGCCUUCUAUUAUUUGUUGAUCUAUUUCUUUUAUCACCAAUUUAUUAAGGCAUAGACUUAUGAAUUUCUUCCUCCUACCCUUAACAGUCUAUAAUUAUAGCUUACUGGGAGAAGAAGCCUCAGGAGCCAAUACUAGCCAGAAUUCUUAAACUGUAAUUGGUGAAUUGCUGGACACUCAGUGUAAACUAGCAUUGAAGGAAAAACUCCCACACUUUCAUGAGUUUUAUCUCCUGGAACCUUACCAGGUUCUCACAGUGAAGAUCAGAGAUCAGAGAAAAAUACUCUCCCUGCUUUGGGCAGGAGGGAAGGAAAAAUAACCAUUCUGAAAUAGCCCUGAGCACAUGUCCUCCAUAAUAGGAAACUACUUUACCAGAGCCUUAUCUGGCUUGGAGAAAGGGCAAUUAGUCAACUACAGACCCCUCUAGCCUUACUGCCUCACACAGGAGAAUAAAAGAGGCUAAGAAACUCUUGUAAAUAUUACAUUUUAGAGACACAGGCCCAAUUAAAAAUAUAUAUAUAUUUAAUAAUAAGAUUAUAGAAUGAUUCCUCUCCUCAAUAUCUUACCACUACAUUAACAGGGCUCCAGUUUUAUACAAGGCACAGAUUCUAUUUGAGAAAGAAUUUAUAGGGAAACCCCAAAACAUCAGGAGAAACAAAAAUAAGGACACUAGAGGAAAGCCUCUGAUACCUACAGCUACAGCAAACAUUAAACAUCUAACUCCUAGCCACAUAAAACCUCACACUAAAGACCUAUUCAGCUCAGUUUCUAUUGCCUGAUACAUCAUGUCUAGCUUUCAGCAAAAAAUUUAAAGACAAGCUAAAAGGCAAAGAAAAAAACAACAACAACCACAGUUUGAAGAGACAAAACAAGCAUCAGAACCAGGCUCUGAUAUGGCAGAGAUUUUGGAAGUAUCAGAGUAGGAUAGUAAAGCAACUAUGAUUAAAGGCUCUAAUGGAAAAAGUGCACAAUAUGCAAGAACAGAUGAGUAAUGUAAAUGGAGAGAUAGAAACUUAGAAAGAACCAAAAGGAAUUGCUAGAAAUAAAAACCACUGUAACAGAAAUGAAGAAUGCCUUUGAUGGGCUCAUCAGUAGACUACACACUGGGGAGGAAAGAAUCAGUCAGCUUGGGGGUAUGCCAACAGAAACUUUCUCAAACUGAAGGUCAAAGAGAAAAAAGAAUGGAAAAAAAACCUAACAAAAUAUCUAAGAACUGUGGGACAAUUGCACAAGUGUAACUUAGGCAUAAUGGGACUACUAGAAGAAGAAAAAAGAGAGAAGGGAAAAGCAGCACUAUUUGAACUAAUAAUGGCUGAGAACUGUCCAAAAGAAUAUUGCUAAUGGCCAAAAUGGUAAUUUGAGAUGAAAAAAGCUCUCUUUAAGAAAAAGUUAAGACUUCCAGUUUCCUGUCUGACAUAAAAAAACUCCAAAGUUGUCAGUCCAUCCUAACAAUUAAUAAAUGGCUGAAUACAAUGAAAAUCAACAACUUUUCUUAGAUGCAUAAGAAAACUAAGGUUAGAGGGAAAAUUGCUGUCGCCAAAAUUGAAAAGAUAGAUAAAUACAGACAAUGACAACUUAGCGAAGCAGAGACUCAUGAGCAGAAAUCUGCAAAGAAUCAGUACCAGGGUAGGAAAACCUGAACUGUAACUGACAAAUUGCUGGAGGCUCAGCGUGGACAACUCUUGAAAUGUAAGCAUUCCAGGGAGUCCCAUAGGUGGGCGCAUUCCCACACUUUUGUGAGUUUCACUUCUAGGAGCUCUACUAGAUACAGUGAAAACUGAAGAAAAAUCUCCUCCUCCUUACGGCAGCAGGAAAGGAAAAGUAGUGAUUUUGAAAUAUGCCAGAGAAUUCUGUUCUUUUUCUUUUUCUUUUUUUUUUUUGGAGACAGAGUCUCCUCGCUCUGUUGCCCAGGCUGGAGUGCAAUGACAUGAUCUUGGCUCACUGCAGCUUCCGCCUUCCGGGUUCAAGCGAUUCUCCUGCCUCAGCCUCCCGAGUACCUGUGAUUACAGGCACCUGCCCCCAUGCCCAGCUAAUUUUUGUAUUUUUAGUAGAGACAGGGUUUCACCAUGUUGGCAGGCUGAUCUCAAACUCCUGACCCAGUGAUCCCCACUCCCUCAGCCUCUCAAAGUGCUGGGAUUAAAGGCAUGAACCACUGCGCCUGGCCAAAUUCUGUUACUCUUAACAAGGACUGUCCACAAGGUAAAUUAUUUUCCCAGAGCCUAACCGAUUGGGAUUUCAUUAGAGCUUAGUUAACCUAGGGGAAAAGAAAAACCCAACUUCAGCAACCUGUAACCAUCCUAUCCCACCUAAGGUGGUGGGGGGUGGGGGAAGGGCUGAGAAGCACUUGUGAAGUUCUAAGUCCAGGGGUACAGGCUCACUAAAAGACUGAGACCUAGUCCCCUUAAUCAUAGGACUACAGAACACUUCCCCUCCAUACCUUACUUUAUCACUAUAUUAUAAAAGGCUUAUUUACUGCAGUUCCCUUUAUCCAGUAUAUCACAUCCAGCUUUUAACAUAAAAUUACAAGACUUACUAAAAGGCAAAAAACACAGUUUGAACAGACAGAAUAAGCAUCAGAACGAGAGCCAGACAUGGCAGGAACAUUGGAAUUAUCGGACUAGCAACUUGAAAUAACUACAAAUAAUAUGCUAAGGAAUCUACUAGAAAAAGUAGAUAACAUGCAAGAACAGAUGGGUAAUGUAAGAAGACAGAUGGAAAUUCUAAGAAAGAAUCUAAAUAAAAUGCUAGAGAUAAAGCAUUGUAAUGGAAAGGAAGAAGGCCUUUAAUGGGCUUGUUAGUAGAUGAAACAUAGCUGAAGAAAGAAUCUCUAAGCUUAAGGAUAUUUCAUUAGAAACUUUCAAAACUGGUAAGCAAAGAGAAAAAAGACUGAAAAAAAAAAAACCAGAACAGAACAUCUAAGAACUUUAGGACAGCCACAAAAUGAAUAACAUGUAUGUAAUGAGAAUACUAGAAGGAGAAGAAAGGAAAGAACAGAAGAAUUAUUUGAUUAAGGACUGAGAACUCCCCCCAAACUAAUGUCAGAUAGCAAACCACAGAUCCAGGAAGCUCAGAGAACACAAGCAGAACAAAUGCCAAGAGAAAACUACACAUACGUAUAUCAUUUUCAAACUGCAGAAAAUCAAAGAUAAAGAAAAUAAUUCUUAAAGAAGCCAGGGAAGGGGGGAACCCUUAGCUAUAGCAGAGAAAAAAAAAGAAAUUAAACCUGACUUCUCUGAAAUCAUACAAGCAAGAAGUGGGAUAAAAUAUUUAGCAUUCCGAGAAAAAAACAAAGCAGCCUAAAAUUUGGUACCCUGUGAAAUUAUUCUUCAAAAGUAAAGGAGAAACAAAGAUAUUUUCAAACAAAAAUUGAGUGAAUUUGUUGCUAGCAGGCCUGCCUUGCAAGAAAUAUUAAAAGAAGUUCUUCAGAGAAAAGCAAGAUGAUAUAGGUUGGAAAUUUAGCUCUACAGAAAGAAAGAGAAUCAGAGAAGGAAUAGUGGAGGUAAAAUAAAAACCUUUAUUUUUAUUAUUCUUAAUUGAUCUACUAGAUAACAGUCGGUUCAAAAGAAUAAUGCUAACACUGGUUUUGACUAUGUAUGCUUAGUAUACCUAUGCUUAUGAAUCACUGAAAUGAAUGACAGCCGUGAGACAAGGGGCAUGAGGGAGAAAUCAGGAUUAUUUUGUUAUUAUAAGGUAUUUGCACUAGCCGUGAAGCAAUAUAAUGUUAUUUGAAAGUGGACUUGCAAUAGUUGUAAAUGUAUAUUGCAAACUCUUAGGCAACCGCUAAAAAAAGAAGUAUAAAUAAUAUGCUGGAAAAGGAGAGAAAAUGAAAUAUACAGAAUGCUCAAUUAAAAACCAAAAAAGGCAGAAAAAAUGUGGAAGACAAAAACAGGAAAAAAAAAAACAGUGGCAACAAAUAGAAAACAGUAGCAAAUAUGGUAGAUAUUAUGUAUAUCAGUAAUCAAUUUGAAUGUCAAUGGCCUAAAUGAACCAAUCAAAAGAUAGAGCUUGUCAGAGUGGGUCAAAAACCCAGAUCCAACUAUAUAUUGUCUAUAAGAAACCCACUUUAAAUAUGAAGACAUAUAUAGAUGAAAAGCAAAGGGAUGAAGAAAGAUAUACUAUGCUAACACUAAUAAAAAGAAAGCUGAAAUAGCUAUAUUAAUUUCAGACAAAACAGACAUUAGAGCAAGGAAAGCUACCAGGAGUAAAGAGAGACAUUACAUAAUAAUAAAAGGCCAAUUCUCCAAGAAGACAGAACAAUGCUUAAUGUGUAUGCUCCUAACACAGCAUCAAACUACAUGAGGCAAAACAAAAACUAAUAGAACUACAAGAAGAAAUAGAUGAAUUCAUGUUUACAGUUACAGACUUCAACAUUCCUCUAUUAGAAAUGGACAGAUCUGCCAAGCAGAAAAUCACGGGGUAUACAGUUGAACUCAAUAGCACCACCAAUCAACUGAGAUAAACGUGACAUCUAUAGACUAUCCAACAACAGCACAAUACACAUUCUCAAGUUCACAGGGAACAUCUCAUCAAGACAGAUCACAAUGAAGGCUAUAAAACUCACAUGAGUAAAUGUAAAAAAAGAAAAAUACAAUGUAUGCUUUCGGAUCUCAGUGGAAUUAAACUAAAAAUCAAUAACCCAAAGAUAGCUGGAAAAUCCCAAAAUACUUAGAUAUUAAAUAAUGUACUUCUAACACAUGGGUCAAAGAAGAAAUCACAAGAAAAAAAUUAAAAUAUUUUAAAAUAAAUGAAAAUACAACUUAUCAAAAUUUAUGGAAGGCAGUGAAAGCAAUGCUCAGAGGGGAAUCUAUAGGAUUGAAUACAUAUAACAGGAAAGAAUAAACAUCUAUAAGAUCUGAACUUAUACUUUAAGAAACUAGAGAAAGAGGAGCAAAUGAAAUGAAAAGCAAGCAGAAGAAAAGAGAUAAUAAAUAUAGUAGAAUAUUUAUUAUGUAGAGUAUAUAAUAUACUCUACAUAAUAUAUAUUCUAUUCUAUAUUAUAAACAUAGAGUAGAAACCAAUGAAAUUGAGAACAGGAAACCCACAGAGAAAAAUCAAUGAUGUUAAAAGCUAGUUCUUUGGAAAAAAUCAAUUAAAUUGAUAAACUUCUAGCCAGGUUAAUCAAGAAAAAAAGAGACAACAAGUUACUCAUGGUAGAAAUGAAAUGAGAGGAUUUAACUACAGAUCCCAUGGACAUUAAAAGGAAAAUAAAGAAAUACUAUGAACAACUCUAUGCCCACAAAUUCAAUAACCUAGACAAAAUAGAUUAAUUCUCUAAAAGGUACAAUCUAUCAAAACUCACACAAAAAGAAAUACACAAUCUACAUAAGCCUAUACCUAUUAAGCAACUGAAUCAAUAAUAAAUUUCCAAAACAGAAAGCACCAGGUCCAGAUGGAUUUUCUUGGUGAAUUCUACCAAACAUCAAAGGAAGAAACUAUAUUAAUUAUCUACAAUCUCUUUCAGAAGACAGAAGCAGAGGGAAUACUUCCUAACUCAUUCUAUGAGGCCAGCAUUACCUUAAUACUAAAACCAGACAAAAACACUGUAAGAAAACAAAACCACAGACCAAUAUCUCUCGUGAAUAUAGACACAAAAAUCCUCAGCAAAAUAAUAGCAAAUAAAAUACAACAAUGUCUAAAAAGAUUGCUACACCACAACUAAGUGGGAUUUAUCCAGGUAUGCAAGGCUCAACACUUGAAUAUGAAUUCAUGUAAUCCAUCAUAUCAACAGACUAAGGAAGAAAAAUCACAUGAUAAUAUCAAUAGAUGCAGAAAAAGAUUUGACAAAAUUGAACACCAAUUCACAAUGAAGACUCUCAGCAAACCAGGAACAGAGGGCAAUUUCCUCAACUUGUGAAAGACAAUGAGAAAGCAAGCCAUAGCCUGGGAGAAAAUAUUUGCAAAAGACGUAUCUGAUACAAGACCGUUAUCCCAAACAUACAAAGAACUCAAAAGAAAAUGAACAACCUGAUCACAAAAUGGGCAAAGAUCUGAAAAGACACCUCAACAAAGAAGACAUAGAUGGCAAAUAGGCGUAUGAAGAGAUGCUCAUCAUCAUACAUCAUUAAGAAACUACAAAUUAAAACAAUGACUACACACCUACUACAAUGGUGAAAAUCACAUCCAAAUCACUAAUACCACCAAUUGCUGGCAAGGAUAUGGGGCAACAGGAAUUCUCAUUCACUGCUGGUAGGAACACAAAAUGGUACAGCCACUUUGGAAGACAGCUUGACAGUUUUACACAAAACUAAACACUCUCACCAUAUGUGCCAGCAAUCAUGUUCCUGGGUAUUUAACCAAAUGAUUUGAAAAUCUACGUGCAAACAAAAGCCUGCGCAUGUGUAUUUAUAGCAACUCCAUUCAUAAUUGCCAAAACUUGGAAGUAUCCCAGAUGUCCUUCAGUAGGUGAAUAAACUGUGGUACAUACAGAUAAUGAACAAUUAUUCAGCACUAAAAGGAAAUGAGCUAACAAGCUCUGAAACACAUGAAAGAAACUUAAAUGCAUAUUACUAAGUGAAAUAAGCCAAGCUGGCCUUCCUCUUCACUUUCUUCUUUACUGCCUCGUCUCCUCCCUUAUCACUCCCUUUUCUUCUCUUUGCUCUCUCUUCCUUUCCCCCUUCUUCUUUCCCCUCUUGCCUUUCUUUUUUUCCUCCCACUCUCCCCCUUUUUUCACUCCUCUCUCUCACUGUUUAGUAUUUUCCCUGUUGUACCCCCUUUCUUAAAUAUCCUAUUUUCUCUUCCCUUGCUCUCUCAUGUCCCUGGCCCUACUACCAUGCGCCCCCACCCCUGCCAAAAAGAAAGAAAGAAGCGAAUCUGAAAAGGCUAUACAAUCAGCCCUUCUUAUUUGUGGGUUCUGCAUCUGUGAACUCAACCAACCAUGGAUUGAAAAUAUUUGGGAAAAAAAUCUAAUAAAAAUUAACAAUACAACAACAACAAAAUGAAUGAAAAAACAAUAUAGUAUAACAACCAUUUACACAGCAUUUACACUGUCUUAGGUAUUGUAAGUAAUCUAGAGAUUUAAAGUAUAUGAAGGGAGUAUGGAGGUUAAAUGCAAAUAUAACAAACAUUUUGUAUCAGGGCCUUGAGCAUCCUUGAAUUUUGGUAGAGUUUGGUAGAGUUUGCCUGGCCCUAUUCUGUAUAAUUCUUAAUGUCAUAGACAGGUUCUUGAAAACUGCAACUUUAAAUGAAACAACUAUAAGGAAACCAAUUUUACCAUAGGCUAAUUGAUAUAAGCAAGAGUUAGGUUCUUACAGCAUAUUUCUGGUCAUAAAAACAUCAUUAAACAUCUAAAUAAAGACCCAAGACACUUUUAAUGUUAAAUAUUAAAAUAAAUGUAAGCUACAUAUACAUUUAAGAAAGAUUAAUAAAAACAAGAUGAUUAUUUACAUUAUGUACAUUAAUGAUGAAUACAUGUAGUUCUACAUUUGUCACAAUCUAUAGAAUAUACAACACCAAGAGUAAACCCUAAUGUAAACUAUGGACUUUGGGUGACAAUGAUGUGUCAGUGUGUUCACCAAUUUUAAUAAAUAUACCAGUCUGGUGUGGGAUAUUGACAAUAAGGGGCGUGGGGUGCAGAGAGCAUAUGGGAACUCUCUCUACAUUCUGCUCGAUUUUGCUUUGAACCUAAAACUGCUUUAAAUAAUACAAUUUUUUUUUUUUACAAGAGUUAAGAGCUAUACAAUCAUGUAUACUUGAAUUCUUGAUUUUCAGGCCUACCUCUCUCUUAACCCAAUAAUGUCGGUUAAGCAUUCAAGAUCCUAAAGUAAAAUCCUGAAAGUCUAAAAAGAGUAUACGGGACUAAAAGUCCUGCUAGGCAACUGUAGGUGAUCACUUAUACCCCUGCUGGAAAAGCUUAAACACUGGUUUUCCAAAGACUUCUUGGUCAUCUGAUAAAUUUAAGAUUCUUAACAUAAACUUUGCUCCCUCUGGAAACCUCACAGCUAAAGGUAAAAGUGAAGAUACCAGCCUGGACAACAUAGGGAGACCCAAUCCCUAAAAAAAUGUUAAAAAAUUAGCCAGGCAUGGUGGUGCAUGCAGGUAGUCCCAGCUACUCUGGAGGCUGAGGUGGGAGGAUUGUUUGAGCCCAGGAGUUUGAGAUUACAGUGAGCUAUGACGACGUCACUGUACUCCAGCCUGGGAAACAGAGCAAGUGAGAAUUCAUCUAAAAAAAAAAAAAAAAAGUAAUAGUUGGAUAGCUGUGUUUCUUACCUCUCUU